GUGAAGCUCCGCGGUGCCUGAUGGGGCCGUUGGGCGGCCGGUAGCUGUUGCUGUUGGGGGACCCCCUCAUUCCUGCCGCUGCCGUCCCUGCUGCCUCAUGGCGGCCAUCGGAGUUCACCUGGGCUGCACCUCAGCCUGUGUGGCCGUCUAUAAGGAUGGCCGGGCUGGUGUGGUUGCAAAUGAUGCCGGUGACCGAGUUACUCCAGCUGUUGUUGCUUACUCAGAAAAUGAAGAGAUUGUUGGAUUGGCAGCAAAACAAAGUAGAAUAAGAAAUAUUUCAAAUACAGUAAUGAAAGUAAAGCAGAUCCUGGGCAGAAGCCAGAAAUGCGGUCCUUGGACCUGGCUUCUCAGCAAUUAUCCCUGAGAGGGAAGAUCCUGGAGAUAUCCUGAGAGCACACAGAGCUUCCCCACACCUUCAGACUUGCACCUUGCUGUCCAGAAGCUGCCUAGCCCUCCUUUCCAACCCACAAUGGCCAGUGCCAAUAGCAGUGCGGGCAUCCGGUGGUCCAGACAGGAGACACGAACUCUUCUCUCCAUACUAGGCGAGGCAGAGUAUAUUCAGCGCCUCCAGACUGUGCAUCACAAUGCAGAUGUCUAUCAGGCUGUGUCUAAGCGAAUGCAGCAGGAGGGCUUCCGCCGCACCGAACGUCAGUGCCGCUCCAAGUUUAAAGUUCUGAAGGCAUUAUAUUUAAAGGCCUAUGUUGCCCAUGCCACAAGUAUGGGUGAGCCACCACACUGUCCAUUUUAUGAUACGUUGGAUCAGCUUCUCCGAAAUCAGAUAGUGACUGACCCAGACAACUUAAUGGAGGAUGCUGCUUGGGCCAAGCACUGUGAUCAGAACUUAGUGGCCUCUGACGCCCCAGGGGAAGAGGGAACCGGCAUUCUAAAAUCAAAAAGGACUCAGGCAGCUGAUCAUCAGCCUAUCUUGAAAACAGUUAAGGCAUCAGAUGAGGAUUGUCAGCUAAGAAUCAGUGACCGGAUACGAGAAACCAGUGACCUUGAGGACUCCUGGGAUGAAUCCUCGGGUGCAGGGUGCUCUCAAGGGACCCCCAGCUACAGCAGCUCCCACAGCCUUUUCAGAGGUGCAGUUGCUCCCUGUCAGAGCAGCCCCAUGGCCAGACUGGGUGUGUCCGGGGAGCCCAGCCCCUGCACCAGCACCAACCGCAGCACUCCUGGGGUAGCCUCCACACCGCAGACUCCAGUCUCCUCUUCGAGAGCUGGUUUUGUUUCUGGUGGGGAUAGGCCCUUGACCAGUGAGCCCCCUCCAAGGUGGGCAAGGCGAAGAAGGCGGUCAGUGGCCAGGACUAUCGCAGCCGAGUUGGCAGAAAACAGGCGAUUGGCACGAGAACUCUCAAAGCGGGAGGAAGAAAAACUGGACAGGCUGAUUGCUAUUGGUGAGGAGGCCAGUGCUCAGCAAGAUACUGCCAAUGAGCUCCGCAGGGAUGCUGUCAUCGCAGUCAGACGUUUGGCAACAGCAGUGGAAGAGGCAACUGGUGCUUUUCAGCUAGGCCUUGAAAAAUUGCUUCAGAGGUUGAUUUCGAAUACCAAAAGCUAGGAACCAAUUACAAAAGGCUCUGCUUCCUAAACUGGUAGAAGUCUAGUUCCCAAACCUGCCUUCUGAAUCCCUGGCUCCUUUUCUGUGUCCUCAGAAAAAAACAUGGAUGAACCAUUUAUAUCCAGAUAGUAUGAAAAUAAUUGCUAGUUCAUUUUCCCAAGAUUCUCCACCAAAUGGAAGACCUUUCAGAAAUGCCAGGGGUGACCUAAUAGAAAACGAUGGAGCCACGUUCUAGACAGCUGGUUCAUCCUAGCUUUGUCACAGAUGUGAAGCAGUUUACCUCCCUCCAGUGGUUUCCUCAUCCGUAAAAUGGGGAUCAAUAAUAACUCCUGCCCUGCCUACCUCACAGGGUUGUUGUGAGGAUCACGUAGUUCAUAGAUGUGAAAGGGUUUAAAAGUUUAAAAGCACUGUACACAUUUAAGUUAUUAAUUCAUAUGGCCUUGGCUGAGGUAAGGCAGAUUGGUUUACAAGAUACAGAAGUAUGGAUAUAUACUGUGACUUCAUUGCUUGAAUCUUUCCUUUGCUGGUCUAACUUGACUGCUUCAUGGAGUUUGAAAUCUUAAUUUUUAAAAUCCCUGUGUGGCUCAUUAGACGACUAUAAGCACAACCUGUAUUUGUACCUUAAUCUCUUACAUUUCCACUGCUGUGUAUCUGACAUAUCUACUAGUAAGCACUGUUUUGUCAAACCGUCUUUCUCUCCUUCAUUUUACUGGUUCUUAGUCUCCUAUCAAUAUAAGGAAAUAAGAAGUGCCAGGGAGCCGCCAUUGUGUGUUACGGUUUAUAUCGAUAAUCUUCAAUAUAAAAUACUGGCCAUUUUAUAAAAUAUUAAAUAUAUGUAAAUUCUUUGCAUUUCAUAUUAUUUGGGUCCCUUUAUAUGCCUAAAUUACAUCUUUAAGUUUCGGUUGCCAUUGGAACAUUGUGGAAACAAUUCAGAUUAUAUCAGUUUCCCAUCCGCUUUUUAGCUGAUUUCAUUCUUUUCUGUUAUUUUUUUGUCUAGUAUGUUAUACAGGGCAAGCCCUAGAAACGUUUCCUUUUGAGGAGCUUUCCAAGAUUCCUUUUCCUCAGAUGUUGUAGACAGAAGUUUAUGUAGUUAAUGGCAUCUGGUGGAAGAGAACAGCUUUGUUUCCUCUUUAACUUUGGGAACACUAGAGGAUGGUGUGGAUAAAGAUUGCCUGCAAUAGAUGACUCCUUUUAAGCACUAGCCGUGAACAGAUGAGCCUCCUCCACACCCCAGACACACACUGGGGAGAGAUGAAGGUGAUAAGCCACACUUCCGAUUUACUCUAGAAGGGAAGACAUUACUCUCUGUCAUUAAACUAACUUAAAGCUUUUAGUGAUUUACUUAGUACUUUUAGGAAUACAAAUAGGAAUCUUUAGGAUUUAAAAAGUUUUCCAAUAAUCUAGAAGUUGGAAAAAUAACAAAGAGUGGGCAUGUUGGGGGAGGUUUUAUUUUCUAUCUUGCAGGCUCGAGUGCUUAGCUAAAUGCUGGAAAUGGACAUAGGUGGAGAAAUGGUCAGAGCAGCAGUGGGAGCGUACCCAGAACCAUGAGUAGACGGCAAGCGAGCUGCUCUGCCAAGCCAGGGAUGGAGGUGUGAGGCGGCUGGUGUGGUAGAAUAUGUUGGAAUCUAGUUAGAAUUCCUGGAUUGGAAUCCUGUCACAGUUUGUUUCAUCAGACAAAUCACUUGCCCUUUUCUAUUAUUAUUAUUUUUUUUUUUUUGAGAAAAAGUCUCACUGUUUUGCCCAGGCUGGGGUGCAGUGGUGCAAUCUUGGCUCACUGCAACCUCAGCCUCCCGAGUAGCCGGGAUUACAGGUGCAUGCCAACAUGCCCAACUCAUUUUUGUAUUUUUAGUAGAGACGGGGUUUCACCAUGUUGGCCAGGCUAGUCUUGAACUCCUGACCUCAGGUGAUCCACCUGCCUCGGCCUCCCAAAGUGCUGAGAUUACAGGCGUGAGCCACCGUGCCCAGCCAAUUCAUGCCUCAAUUUCUUUAUCUCCGGAUUGAGGGAUUUGUAUUAGAUUUUUUUUUUCCUAGUACCUUCCAGCUCUAAAAAAAUUUGAAAUAGCAUAAUAAAAGACAAAAUGAAAACGAAAUUUUAAUUGUAAUAUUUUCUGUCACAGCAGCAUAUGUAUAUUUGAAAUACUGGUAACAAUUUUAAGGUAGCAUUCUGUGGUAUUAAUAUUUAUUAAUAUGCUCAUGAACUUCUAAGUGCCACACCAGACAUAUAGACUCUUUACUUUAAAAGAGCAUAUAUUUAAGGCAUUGAAAUGGAUACAGCUAUAUUCAUUCUCAAUUGUCUUAGGCUAUUAUAUGGAAAGAUAUGUGUCAAUUAUAGGUAGGUAGGUAGGUAGGUAGAUUUUCUGGAAACACAGAAGUACUUGACGGAGAGUUAGGCCUGUAUUCUAUAAAUCUAUUAAUGGUAGCAAAGUGCAUAAGACAGGGAUUUCUUUGAGAUGAAAGGAGUGCUGAAGAAGAGCAUUGGAAUUAAUAUUUGGAUGUGGUAUUGUGAAAUUCAAUGGGUAAAGUAACCCUAAUGUGGGAAUAAAAGUCAAGGGAAAGGUCUUGAAUAAGUACACAGAAAAAUAGGCUAAAAAUAUUAAGGGGAGGGAAAUUGGAAUACAGGGAGACAGUGUGCAAGAAAGCAAGCCAGGAAUCUGCCUAUGUGGUAGACCCAACCAUUACUACUUGAACCCCCUUAGAAAAGCUUUUCCAGCAUUCCAUAACUCAGGUUCCUCAUUUAUAAAGUGGGAAACUCAUAAUUGUCCUACCUACCUCACAGGGGUGUUGUGAGGAUCAAAGGAACAGAUGAAUGUAUGAGCACUUUCAGACAUGUAAGGCACUGUCAUGUAACAAGUAGGGGAAAGACUCUGGAGCACAUUAGUGCUGGUGUGUGCCAAGCCCGUGGGCUGUUGACCGUAAGGGAUAUUCAAGUAGGAGGAGGAAGAGAAGAUGGCAUUGCUAAUAAAGGUUGUGAUACACAACCAUAGGAUUAACUGCCUCCUCAAGUCCAUCAUGUAAAUAAGGUGCUAUGUAUACCAACUUCUCACCACCUUUGUUUUUCUGUUCGGUAAUCCUGGUGUGGACAAAUAAAGUUUUCACUUGUAUGUA